GGUCGCGGAGCUGCGGCCAGCUUUGGGAGGGCCGGCCCCGGGAUGUGAGUGCCGCGGGGCGAGGGCGGGGGUGGGCUCCCAGGGGUCCCGGUGGGCGGGCGCGCUAGGGCGAGGGCGGGGACGGCCGGGCGGGCGCGCCAGGCUACACACAACCCAGCUGUACCAGCAUGUGCCAGAGACACGCUGGCCAAUCGUGUACUCGCCGCGCUACAACAUCACCUUCAUGGGCCUGGAGAAGCUGCAUCCCUUUGAUGCCGGAAAAUGGGGCAAAGUGAUCAAUUUCCUAAAAGAAGAGAAGCUUCUGUCUGACAGCAUGCUGGUGGAGGCGCGGGAGGCCUCGGAGGAGGACCUGCUGGUGGUGCACACGAGGCGCUAUCUUAAUGAGCUCAAGAGGAAGGUGCUGAGGCCCCUUCGGACCCAGACAGGAGGAACCAUAAUGGCGGGGAAGCUGGCUGUGGAGCGAGGCUGGGCCAUCAACGUGGGGGGUGGCUUCCACCACUGCUCCAGCGACCGUGGCGGGGGCUUCUGUGCCUAUGCGGACAUCACGCUCGCCAUCAAGUUUCUGUUUGAGCGUGUGGAGGGCAUCUCCAGGGCUACCAUCAUUGAUCUUGAUGCCCAUCAGGGCAAUGGGCAUGAGCGAGACUUCAUGGACGACAAGCGUGUGUACAUCAUGGAUGUCUACAACCGCCACAUCUACCCAGGGGACCGCUUUGCCAAGCAGGCCAUCAGGCGGAAGGUGGAGCUGGAGUGGGGCACAGAGGAUGAUGAGUACCUGGAUAAGGUGGAGAGGAACAUCAAGAAAUCCCUCCAGGAGCACCUGCCCGACGUGGUGGUAUACAAUGCAGGCACCGACAUCCUCGAGGGGGACCGCCUUGGGGGGCUGUCCAUCAGCCCAGCGGGCAUCGUGAAGCGGGAUGAGCUGGUGUUCCGGAUGGUCCGUGGCCGCCGGGUGCCCAUCCUUAUGGUGACCUCAGGCGGGUACCAGAAGCGCACAGCCCGCAUCAUUGCUGACUCCAUACUUAAUCUGUUUGGCCUGGGGCUCAUUGGGCCUGAGUCACCCAGCGUCUCCGCACAGAACUCAGACACACCGCUGCUUCCCCCUGCAGUGCCCUGACCCUUGCUGCCCUGCCUGUCACGUGGCCCUGCCUAUCCGCCCCUUAGUGCUUUUUGUUUUCUAACCUCAUGGGGUGGUGGAGGCAGCCUUCAGUGAGCAUGGAGGGGCAGGGCCAUCCCUGGCUGGGGCCUGGAGCUGGCCCUUCCUCUACUUUUCCCUGCUGGAAGCCAGAAGGGCUUGAGGCCUCUAUGGGUGGGGGCAGAAGGCAGAGCCUGUGUCCCAGGGGGACCCACACGAAGUCACCAGCCCAUAGGUCCAGGGAGGCAGGCAGUUAACUGAGAAUUGGAGAGGACAGGCUAGGUCCCAGGCACAGCGAGGGCCCUGGGCUUGGGGUGUUCUGGUUUUGAGAACGGCAGACCCAGGUCGGAGUGAGGAAGCUUCCACCUCCAUCCUGACUAGGCCUGCAUCCUAACUGGGCCUCCCUCCCUCCCCUUGGUCAUGGGAUUUGCUGCCCUCUUUGCCCCAGAGCUGAAGAGCUAUAGGCACUGGUGUGGAUGGCCCAGGAGGUGCUGGAGCUAGGUCUCCAGGUGGGCCUGGUUCCCAGGCAGCAGGUGGGAACCCUGGGCCUGGAUGUGAGGGGCGGUCAGGAAGGGGUACAGGUGGGUUCCCUCAUCUGGAGUUCCCCCUCAAUAAAGCAAGGUCUGGACCUGCCUUCCCAGGCCCUUCUGUGGGGGUGAAGGUGGGGAAGGCCUGCGGCGCCCAGAUCACUGCCUUAGCAGUAGUCUUGCCUGUUCAGUGCAAGGGGCAGGUUUUGGGGGGAGGAAUUCUUAGCGCAAGGACGGGCCUCAGCCCUGUCGCCUCCAGGGGGCCGCUGACCCAGGUGGGGAGAGGGCAGAAGAAGGGUGGGGGACGUGGGCAGGCCAGGCUCACAGGUGGAAAUCAGGGAUGCAGGGUGGUGCCCAAGCCAGGUCCUGCAGGAACCCAGGCCCAGGGAGGGACCCAGACACUGGUGAGGCGGGGCAGGGGUUCCUGGAGAGAGGGCAGCGAGGAUCUCUAUCCUGGCCUGGGGAUUAUGAACAUAGGUAGCCGGGGCAGGGCCCUGGGUGGGACUGUGGCCUCCACUGGCCUCACCAAAGUGCCUGGGCCCCAAUCCUUCUCCAUGCCCAGGGGCCCCAGGUGGGCCAGACCUCUGGCCUGUUCCUCAGCCCUACUCAUGGGGACAUUCAGGGACCUCCAGGAAGUGGGCGGGGGAGCAUCCACCCCUGCUAGCCGGCAGCUGUGGCCCUGAUCAAAUCAGGGGCUGGGGAGGGAAAGUGGGUCCAUUGAGGUGGCCCUGCUCCAUCAGCCCCCUACGGGACUUGUGUUCAUUACAGUGAGGGGGUGCUCCCACUGUCUCCCGGCCUCCCUAAUGCUCCCUCUGCUGCAGGGAGAAGGGUUCCAAGAUCACAAAAUGUCAACAAUGCUGGCCUCCUGGACCAGACCCCGAGGCUCUAACAAUGCACUCUGAGAUCCCUACCCUUGCCGUUGGUCUCUGUCGCUGACUCGAGGCACCUAACAUCCAUUCACACCCAACACAGGCCAGCGACUUCUGGGGCUCAGCCACAGACAUGGUUUGUCACUGUUGAGCUUCUGUUCCUAGAGAAUCCUAGAGGCUUGAUUGGCCCAGGCUGCUGUGUGUGCUGGAGGCAAAGAAUCCCUACCUCCUAGGGGUGAAAGGAAAUGAAAAUGGAAAGUUCUUGUAGCGCAAGGCCUGACAUGGGUAGCUGCUCAAUAAAUGCUAGUGUGUUAUUUCA